AGGCACUCCCUGGGCUAAACAGCAUCACCAUGUCUGUUCGAUACAGCUCAAGCAAGCACUACUCUUCCUCCCGCAGUGGAGGAGGAGGAGGAGGAGGAGGAUGUGGAGGAGGAGGAGGAGUGUCAUCCCUAAGAAUUUCUAGCAGCAAAGGCUCCCUUGGUGGAGGAUUUAGCUCAGGGGGGUUCAGUGGUGGCUCUUUUAGCCGUGGGAGCUCUGGUGGGGGCUGCUUUGGGGGCUCAUCAGGUGGCUAUGGAGGAUUAGGAGGUUUUGGUGGAGGUAGCUUUCGUGGAAGCUAUGGAAGUAGCAGCUUUGGUGGGAGUUAUGGAGGCAUCUUUGGAGGGGGCAGUUUCGGAGGUGGCAGCUUUGGUGGGGGCAGCUUUGGUGGAGGCGGCUUUGGUGGAGGCGGCUUUGGAGGAGGCUUUGGUGGUGGAUUUGGAGGAGAUGGUGGCCUUCUCUCUGGAAAUGAAAAAGUAACCAUGCAGAAUCUGAAUGACCGCCUGGCUUCCUACUUGGACAAAGUUCGGGCUCUGGAAGAAUCAAACUAUGAGCUGGAAGGCAAAAUCAAGGAGUGGUAUGAAAAGCAUGGCAACUCACAUCAGGGGGAGCCUCGUGACUACAGCAAAUACUACAAAACCAUCGAUGACCUUAAAAAUCAGAUUCUCAACCUAACAACUGAUAAUGCCAACAUCCUGCUUCAGAUCGACAAUGCCAGGCUGGCAGCUGAUGACUUCAGGCUGAAGUAUGAGAAUGAGGUAGCUCUGCGCCAGAGCGUGGAGGCUGACAUCAACGGCCUGCGUAGGGUGCUGGAUGAGCUGACCCUGACCAAGGCUGACCUGGAGAUGCAAAUUGAGAGCCUGACUGAAGAGCUGGCCUAUCUGAAGAAGAACCACGAGGAGGAAAUGAAAGACCUUCGAAAUGUGUCCACUGGUGAUGUGAAUGUGGAAAUGAAUGCUGCCCCGGGUGUUGAUCUGACUCAACUUCUGAAUAACAUGAGAAGCCAAUAUGAACAACUUGCUGAACAAAACCGCAAAGAUGCUGAAGCCUGGUUCAAUGAAAAGAGCAAGGAACUGACUACAGAAAUUGAUAAUAACAUUGAACAGAUAUCCAGCUAUAAAUCUGAGAUUACUGAAUUGAGACGUAAUGUACAAGCUCUGGAGAUAGAACUACAGUCCCAACUGGCCUUGAAACAAUCCCUGGAAGCCUCCUUGGCAGAAACAGAAGGUCGCUACUGUGUGCAGCUCUCACAGAUUCAGGCCCAGAUAUCCGCUCUGGAAGAACAGUUGCAACAGAUUCGAGCUGAAACCGAGUGCCAGAAUACUGAAUACCAACAACUCCUGGAUAUUAAGAUCCGACUGGAGAAUGAAAUUCAAACCUACCGCAGCCUGCUAGAAGGAGAGGGAAGUUCCGGAGGCGGCGGACGCGGCGGCGGAAGUUUCGGCGGCGGCUACGGCGGCGGAAGCUCCGGCGGCGGAAGCUCCGGCGGCGGCCACGGCGGCGGCCACGGCGGCAGUUCCGGCGGCGGCUACGGAGGCGGAAGCUCCGGCGGCGGAAGCUCCGGCGGCGGCUACGGGGGCGGAAGCUCCAGCGGCGGCCACGGCGGCAGUUCCAGCGGCGGCUACGGUGGUGGCAGUUCCGGCGGCGGCGGCGGCGGCUACGGGGGCGGCAGCUCCGGCGGCGGCAGCAGCUCCGGCGGCGGAUACGGCGGCGGCAGCUCCAGCGGAGGCCACAAGUCCUCCUCUUCCGGGUCCGUGGGCGAGUCUUCAUCUAAGGGACCAAGGUCAGCAGAAACUAGCUGGGAUACUAACAAAACCAGAGUAAUCAAGACAAUUAUUGAAGAGGUGGCGCCCGACGGUAGAGUUCUUUCAUCUAUGGUUGAAUCAGAAACCAAGAAACACUACUAUUAAACUGCAUCAAGAGGAAAGAGUCUCCCUUCACACAGACCAUUAUUUACAGAUGCAUGGAAAACAAAGUCUCCAAGAAAACACUUCUGUCUUGAUGGUCUAUGGAAAUAGACCUUGAAAAUAAGGUGUCUACAAGGUGUUUUGUGGUUUCUGUAUUUCUUCUUUUCACUUUACCAGAAAGUGUUCUUUAAUGGAAAGAAAAACAACUUUCUGUUCUCAUUUACUAAUGAAUUUCAAUAAACUUUCUUACUGAUGCAAACUA